ACUGUCGCUUCAGCCAGGCUGCGGAGCGGACGGACGCGCCUGGUGCCCCGGGGAGGGGCGCCACCGGGGGAGGAGGAGGAGGAGAAGGUGGAGAGGAAGAGACGCCCCCUCUGCCCGAGACCUCUCAAGGCCCUGACCUCAGGGGCCAGGGCACUGACAGGACAGGAGAGCCAAGUUCCUCCACUUGGGCUGCCCGAAGAGGCCGCGACCCUGGAGGGCCCUGAGCCCACCGCACCAGGGGCCCCAGCACCACCCCGGGGGCCUAAAGCGACAGUCUCAGGGGCCAUCGCAAGGUUUCCAGUUGCCUAGACAACAGGCCCAGGGUCAGAGCAACAAUCCUUCCAGCCACCUGCCUCAACUGCUGCCCCAGGCACCAGCCCCAGUCCCUACGCGGCAGCCAGCCCAGGUGACAUGCCGGUGCUCUCCAGGCCCCGGCCCUGGCGGGGGAACACGCUGAAGCGCACGGCCGUGCUCCUGGCCCUCGCGGCCUAUGGAGCCCACAAAGUCUACCCCUUGGUGCGCCAGUGCCUGGCCCCGGCCAGGGGUCUUCAGGCGCCCGCCGGGGAGCCCACGCAGGAGGCCUCCGGGGUCGCGGCGGCCAAAGCUGGCAUGAACCGGGUAUUCCUGCAGCGGCUCCUGUGGCUCCUGCGGCUGCUGUUCCCCCGGGUCCUGUGCCGGGAGACGGGGCUGCUGGCCCUGCACUCGGCCGCCUUGGUGAGCCGCACCUUCCUGUCGGUGUAUGUGGCCCGCCUGGACGGAAGGCUGGCCCGCUGCAUCGUCCGCAAGGACCCGCGGGCUUUUGGCUGGCAGCUGCUGCAGUGGCUCCUCAUCGCCCUCCCUGCUACCUUCGUCAACAGUGCCAUCCGUUACCUGGAGGGCCAACUGGCCCUGUCGUUCCGCAGCCGUCUGGUGGCCCACGCCUACCGCCUCUACUUCUCCCAGCAGACCUACUACCGGGUCAGCAACAUGGACGGGCGGCUUCGCAACCCUGACCAGUCUCUGACGGAGGACGUGGUGGCCUUUGCGGCCUCUGUGGCCCACCUCUACUCCAACCUGACCAAGCCACUCCUGGACGUGGCUGUGACUUCCUACACCCUGCUUCGGGCGGCCCGCUCCCGUGGAGCCGGCACAGCCUGGCCCUCGGCCAUCGCCGGCCUCGUGGUGUUCCUCACGGCCAACGUGCUGCGGGCCUUCUCGCCCAAGUUCGGGGAGCUGGUGGCAGAGGAGGCGCGGCGGAAGGGGGAGCUGCGCUACAUGCACUCGCGUGUGGUGGCCAACUCGGAGGAGAUCGCCUUCUAUGGGGGCCAUGAGGUGGAGCUGGCCCUGCUACAGCGCUCCUACCAGGACCUGGCCUCGCAGAUCAACCUCAUCCUUCUGGAACGCCUGUGGUAUGUUAUGCUGGAGCAGUUCCUCAUGAAGUAUGUGUGGAGCGCCUCGGGCCUGCUCAUGGUGGCUGUCCCCAUCAUCACUGCCACUGGCUACUCAGAGUCAGAUGCAGAGGCCGUGAAGAAGGCAGCCUUGGAAAAGAAGGAGGAGGAGCUGGUGAGCGAGCGCACAGAAGCCUUCACUAUUGCCCGCAACCUCCUGACAGCGGCUGCAGAUGCCAUUGAGCGGAUCAUGUCGUCGUACAAGGAGGUGACGGAGCUGGCUGGCUACACAGCCCGGGUGCACGAGAUGUUCCAGGUAUUUGAAGAUGUUCAGCGCUGUCACUUCAAGAGGCCCAGGGAGCUAGAGGACGCUCAGGCGGGGUCUGGGACCAUAGGCCGGUCUGGUGUCCGUGUGGAGGGCCCCCUGAAGAUCCGAGGGACCUCCAUGUGCUUCUGGCCCAUCCCAGUCCACCCAGGACGGGAGGGCUGCCGGGCAGGGUCUUUGAGGACUUCGGCCUGGUCGAGCUGGGCCCCUGGAGGGUUUCCUGCAGAGAGGUGCUGGUCCGCCCGCCUUCCUUCCCAGACAGUAGCUGCCGGCCACCGUACUGACUCGCCCUUUGAGGGCCUCAGCCUGGAUUAUUCAUUCAAAACAAGGGGGAUGUGGUCCCCUCACCCAUGCAGGACAGCAAGAGAAAGUUCCAGUCAGUGUGCCAGCUGCUGGCUGCCACGGGAGGCAGGCCAGGUGGUGGAUGUGGAACAGGGGAUCAUCUGCGAGAACAUCCCCAUCGUCACGCCCUCAGGAGAGGUGGUGGUGGCCAGCCUCAACAUCAGGGUGGAGGAAGGCAUGCAUCUGCUCAUCACAGGCCCCAAUGGCUGCGGCAAGAGCUCCCUGUUCCGGAUCCUGGGUGGGCUCUGGCCCACGUACGGUGGUGUGCUCUACAAGCCCCCACCCCAGCGCAUGUUCUACAUCCCGCAGAGGCCCUACAUGUCUGUGGGCUCCCUGCGUGACCAGGUGAUCUACCCGGACUCAGUGGAGGACAUGCAAAGGAAGGGCUACUCGGAGCAGGACCUGGAAGCCAUCCUGGACGUCGUGCACCUGCACCACAUCCUGCAGCGGGAGGGAGGUUGGGAGGCUAUGUGUGACUGGAAGGACGUCCUGUCGGGUGGCGAGAAGCAGAGAAUCGGCAUGGCCCGCAUGUUCUACCACAGGCCCAAGUACGCCCUCCUGGAUGAAUGCACCAGCGCCGUGAGCAUCGACGUGGAAGGCAAGAUCUUCCAGGCGGCCAAGGACGCGGGCAUUGCCCUGCUCUCCAUCACCCACCGGCCCUCCCUGUGGAAAUACCACACACACUUGCUACAGUUCGAUGGGGAGGGCGGCUGGAAGUUCGAGAAGCUGGACUCAGCUGCCCGCCUGAGCCUGACGGAGGAGAAGCAGCGGCUGGAGCAGCAGCUGGCGGGCAUUCCCAAGAUGCAGCGGCGCCUCCAGGAGCUCUGCCAGAUCCUGGGCGAGGCCGUGGCCCCAGCGCAUGUGCCGGCACCUAGCCCGCAAGGCCCUGGUGGCCUCCAGGGUGCCUCCACCUGACACAACCGUCCCCGGCCCCUGCCCCGCCCCCAAGCUCGGAUCACAUGAAGGAGACAGCAGCACCCACCCAUGCACGCACCCCGCCCCUGCAUGCCUGGCCCCUCCUCCUAGAAAACCCUUCCCGCCCUCGGGAAAGUAGAUGUGGAGGGUGGCGCCCUGCGUAACCCUCGCCCUGUCCCUCCCACUCCCUGGGGGCGCUGUUCCACAGUGACUGGGCCCUGUCCAGGGCAGUGAGUCCUCUACUUUGCUCCGUGGAGGAAGCUGGGGUACAAGGGGCCCAGUGCUGGCCACACAGCAGCGCAGCCGAGCCCCAGGAGCCCGUCAGGCCACAGCCCCUGGCACUGCAGGUGGCCUCCCUCCAGAGACUCGAGUCCCCAUGAUUCCCUCCUCGUCAGUCUCUCAAAGACCCCAUGGUCCAUCCCCUGAGGGUGGUCAGCCAAGGCUCCCGUUCCGUGGGAUGCCAUAAAAGCCGCCCAGUGGGACCCACAGUCACACAGAGCGCCUCACCUGCAUCCUCUCCCCCACAAGAGCCCCAAAGAUCCCACGGGAGAGGGGAGAGGGACGCACAGCACUGCCUGCCAAGCGAGAAUGCAGGCCCCGCCCCCUCGGCCCCUCACCACCUCUUUCUACAGCCUAAUUUAUUGGAUUCCCUAUUCGUAGCCAUCUCCGUGGCCAAUGUGACUACCGUGCCAGCAGCGGGGGCGGCCCAGCCUCUGAGUCCCGUGGGGCCCCGGCUCCCACCGGUGCCAAACCCAGCCCCUGCGGCCGUCACCCCGCCAGCCUACACUGCCAGCCGCCACCGGGGCACACGGGCCUCUGCUUGCCAGCCAGGAGUGCGGACACCAUGUUCCCAGCUCAGUGCCAAAGAGGGGUCACCAGGGGGAGCUGUCUGCGGAGCCAGCGCCUGCCCGAGAGAGACCCCACCGCCACCGUGUGCCUUUCCCGGGCCCUCAGCCCUCGGGCCGGGCACCACCCCCAGUCCCCCCAGUAAAAGCCUCCACUGGCAAAUGCAGUCCUUCC